GCUCCCGUCGUGGCGACGGUGGCGGCGAGCGGCGUCAGAGCUUGAGGGGGGGUUGACGGCUUCUGGCGGGUGGCGGUGUUGAAGGCGAGAGCUUGCUUGGCCCGUGUCGCUUCUGUCCCAAGAACCGGACGGAGAGUGAGGGCACGAGGGUCGCUGUCGGGGGCUGUCGUCUUCCACGUACACGUCGUCGUGAGGAGCGCAGUCCGGACUCUUCCCGCAACCCCUCCGGCUCCCUUUCCGCACGCCUCGAGGCGGCGGCGGCCACCGAGACAGCAGCGCACCUUCCCCCAUCCCUUCCCCUUAUCCCCCAGCCCAAAAGGGCCCGGUCUGCGCCCCACCCCCGCCCGUCCGCCCGCUACGCCGCCGCCAUGUCGGCGCAGGCCCAGAUGCGCGCGAUGCUGGACCAGUUGAUGGGCACCUCCCGGGACGGUUCAAUGUAUCUAUGCCUGCCUACCUCAAUCUGCAAGGGAGUGUCAGAAAGGCCCCGCAUUCGCCAAGCCGAGAUACAACUCGUCAACGAAUCAAAUUCAGUGAUGACAGAGUAUGCAAGAGUCACCUUCUCAACUGUUGUCCUCAUGAUGUCCUUUCUGGAACUAGAAUGGAUCUUGGAGAAUGUCUGAAAGUCCAUGACCUGGCUUUAAGAGCGGAUUAUGAAAUUGCAUCCAAAGAACAAGAUUUUUUCUUUGAACUUGAUGCCAUGGAUCAUCUGCAGUCAUUCAUUGCAGAUUGUGAUCGUAGAACAGAAGUGGCCAAGAAAAGAUUAGCAGAAACUCAAGAAGAGAUUAGUGCUGAAGUAGCAGCAAAGGCAGAACGUGUUCAUGAGUUAAAUGAAGAAAUUGGUAAAUUGUUAGCCAAGGUGGAACAACUAGGAGCUGAAGGGAAUGUGGAGGAAUCCCAGAAAGUAAUGGAUGAAGUAGAGAAAGCACGGGCAAAGAAAAGAGAAGCAGAGGAAGUUUAUCGGAAUUCUAUGCCAGCUUCCAGUUUUCAGCAGCAGAAACUUCGAGUCUGUGAAGUCUGCUCUGCCUAUUUAGGACUUCAUGAUAAUGACAGACGACUGGCUGAUCAUUUUGGGGGUAAACUGCACCUGGGAUUUAUUGAAAUAAGAGAGAAGCUUGAAGAAUUAAAGAGAGUCGUAGCUGAGAAGCAGGAGAAAAGAAACCAGGAACGGCUGAAACGAAGAGAAGAGAGAGAGAGAGAAGAAAGGGAGAAGCUGAGGAGGUCCCGAUCACACAGCAAGAAUCCAAAAAGAUCCAGGUCCAGAGAGCAUCGCAGACAUCGAUCUCGCUCCAUGUCACGUGAACGCAAGAGGAGAACUCGAUCCAAAUCUCGGGAGAAACGCCAUCGCCACAGGUCCCGCUCCAGCAGCCGUAGCCGCAGCCGUAGCCACCAGAGAAGUCGGCACAGUUCUAGAGAUAGGAGCAGAGAACGAUCCAAGAGGAGAUCCUCAAAAGAAAGAUUCAGAGACCAAGACUUAGCAUCAUGUGACAGAGACAGGAGUUCAAGAGACAGAUCACCUCGUGACAGAGAUCGGAAAGAUAAGAAGCGGUCCUAUGAGAGUGCUAAUGGCAGAUCAGAAGACAGGAGGAGCUCUGAAGAGCGCGAAGCAGGGGAGAUCUAACUAGCUGUGUACAUUUCUUCAGUCCUUAAGCUUCCUACGGAGUUACGUACUAUUGUUUAGUUCACAGCUGUUCAGGGUGACAGUGAGCAGAUCCAGACACCAGAUCCAGCUAGGCUAGAUGUACAGUAUCUAACUUGAUCUGAACUGAACCUGUUUUCCUUGAUGAUGCCUAAAACUACAUCCAUAGUUUCUGGUGAACCUGUAAUACAGUUCUGAAAGUACAGUUUUAUAUAAUAAGAUGCUGAUCUCUUUAUUCUUUCAAGUAAGAGUGCUAGUGAACAAAUUGUGUUACUUGCCUUGGGAUUUUUUGAACGUUUGUAAAAUGCUGUCUUCCUAGUCCAAACAGCUGCAGCUUUGGGCAUUUUUCUUUUUAAUUAUUCUUCCUCUGACUUUGUAUCCCUUAAUACCUACACUCUCCAAUUGUAAGAGAAAGGGGGCAGGGAAGCAAUAUAGCUUCCAUUCUAAGGCUGUAUUCCCGUUAUGAAUUACUAGCUGAUUACAGUUCAGAGCAUUGAUCCUGGAAUGUGUGCUGGAGAAAUUUAAAAUACUGGGGUUUUUUGUUUAAUGGUGCCUAUUUAGAGUUGGAAGUUGAACAGCUGUUGCAUUACAUACUUUUGCUUUUUUAUUGAAAUUUUGAAAUCAAACGUCUUGAUUUUUCUGUUCUGUUGAAUUGCUAUGUUCAGGAUGUUCUAGGGGGUGGGGGCAGGGACUCUUUUCGUAAUAAGCACUUGUUUUAUUUUGUGUGUGUGGAGUAUAAAGGCUACACCCUUAUUGUAAAAAAAUAAUAAUAAUAAAAUGAAAGAAACAAUCACCACCACCAUUAUUAAACUGUAACUUGUCUAGUAAAUUGUCACUAGAACUAUUUGCUGUGGGCAUUUCCUCUAUUCUGUUACGUCAUUAACAGUGCCUUACUGUGCAAGGCACCAAAGGACAUAAAUACGUACUUGCAAAGAUUCCAGAUGAGCUGUUCAUGUGGGCCCCUUGCUGACUAUAUUCCAGCCACUUCAGGGUUGUUUGUAAUGACCGUUAUAGAGAAGGGCUCGACCUGCAGAAGAAACUGGGGUGUUUUUAUUCUCAUUCAACAAACCCAAAUAAAAACAGUAUAUGUAACCAA